ACCGUGGCAACGGACGGCAACAGCUCGGGCGGCGCAUGGAGAGUGCGGGCGGCUUCAAGCUGGGUAUGGAGCCCCUCAGCGGCGGCGGGGUCUGUGAGUUGGACGCGGGGUCUUGGCGGGGAAUGGAGGUAGAAUAAACGUGGGACCCGGAGUGCACCAAGGUGAGAAAAAAAAAUUACUAAAAAUGACAAGUAGAAGACUUGAGGAGUCCAUGGGGGCUGUUCAGAUGGGAUUGGUCAAUAUGUUCAAAGGAUUUCAAAGCAAGGUUUUGCCACCCCUGAGUCCAAAGGUGGUUACAGAAGAAGAAGUAAACCGAAUGCUUACACCCUCAGAGUUCCUGAAGGAAAUGUCCCUGACCACCGAGCAGAGACUGGCAAAAACACGUUUGAUGUGCCGACCACAGAUCAUCGAACUCUUAGAUAUGGGGGAAACAACACAUCAGAAGUUUUCAGGAAUUGACCUGGAUCAGGCAUUAUUCCAGCCCUUUCCAUCAGAAAUUAUAUUUCAGAACUACACUCCCUGUGAAGUCUAUGAAGUUCCACUGAUUUUGAGGAACAAUGACAAAAUUCCAAGGUUGGUGAAAGUUGUGGAAGAAAGUUCGCCUUACUUUAAAGUAAUCAGCCCCAAAGAUAUUGGCCACAAAGUGGCUCCUGGAGUGCCUUCCAUAUUCCGAAUCCUCUUUACUCCAGAGGAGAACAAGGAUUACGCCCAUACGUUGACCUGUGUUACUGAAAGAGAAAAGUUUAUUGUACCCAUCAAAGCUAGAGGGGCACGAGCCAUUCUCGAUUUUCCUGACAAGCUGAAUUUUUCCACUUGUCCUGUCAAAUACAGCACCCAGAAGAUUCUGCUGGUACGAAACAUUGGCAACAAAAAUGCUGUAUUUCACAUCAAAACUUGUAGGCCUUUCUCUAUAGAACCAGCUAUUGGAACUCUUAAUGUGGGAGAGUCCAUGCAACUGGAAGUGGAGUUUGAGCCACAGAGUGUGGGCGAUCACAGUGGAAGACUUAUCGUGUGUUAUGACACAGGUGAAAAGGUGUUUGUAUCUCUCUAUGGAGCUGCCAUAGACAUGAAUAUAAGGCUGGAUAAGAAUUCCUUGACCAUCGAGAAAACCUACAUAUCUCUGGCCAAUCAGCGAACUAUAACCAUUCACAAUCGCAGUAAUAUCAUUGCCCAUUUCCUGUGGAAGGUAUUUGCUACCCAGCAAGAAGAGGACAGAGAAAAAUAUAGGGCCUGUGAUGAUCUGAUCAAAGAGGAGAAGGAUGAGACUGAUGAGUUUUUUGAAGAGUGCAUUACUGAUCCUUUACUCCGAGAACAUCUUUCUGUUCUGUCCCGAACCUUUGCGAAUCAGAGGAGGCUGGUGCAGGGAGACAGCAAGCUGUUCUUCAAUAACGUUUUCACUGUGGAGCCCCUGGAAGGUGAUGUCUGGCCCAACUCAUCAGCUGAAAUCACCGUGUACUUUAACCCACUAGAAGCCAAGCUCUAUCAACAGACCAUUUACUGCGACAUUUUAGGCCGAGAAAUCCGUCUGCCCCUCCGAAUCAAAGGGGAAGGCAUGGGACCUAAGAUUCACUUCAACUUUGAAUUGCUGGAUAUUGGGAAAGUUUUCACUGGAUCUGCACAUUGUUAUGAGGCGAUACUGUACAACAAAGGCAGCAUCGAUGCUCUCUUCAACAUGACCCCUCCAACUUCAGCUUUGGGGGCCUGCUUUGUUUUCAGUCCCAAGGAAGGCAUCAUUGAACCAAGUGGAGUCCAAGCUAUCCAGAUCUCCUUCAGCUCUACCAUCCUGGGAAACUUUGAAGAAGAGUUCCUGGUCAAUGUCAAUGGGUCACCUGAGCCUGUGAAACUGACCAUUAGAGGCUGUGUCAUUGGACCUACCUUCCAUUUUAAUGUUCCAGCUCUGCACUUUGGUGAUGUUUCCUUUGGGUUUCCUCAUACCUUGAUAUGUUCCCUCAAUAAUACCUCUUUGAUCCCCAUGACUUACAAACUGCGUAUCCCUGGGGAUGGCCUUGGCCAUAAAAGCAUUUCAUAUUGUGAGCAGCAUGUGGACUACAAAAGACCAUCUUGGACCAAGGAAGAAAUAUCCUCAAUGAAACCAAAAGAAUUCACCAUCUCUCCUGACUGUGGCACCAUUCGCCCCCAGGGAUUUGCUGCUAUCAGGGUGACAUUAUGCUCCAACACUGUGCAGAAAUACGAGCUGGCACUCGUGGUGGACGUGGAGGGCAUCGGAGAAGAGGUGCUGGCGCUCUUAAUUACAGCAAGGUGUGUUGUACCUGCCCUCCACCUGGUCAAUACAGAGGUGGACUUUGGGCACUGCUUCCUGAAGUACCCGUAUGAGAAAACACUCCAGCUUGCCAAUCAAGAUGACCUCCCAGGAUUCUAUGAGGUCCAGCCUCAGGUGUGUGAGGAGGUGCCUACUGUGCUGUUUUCCAGCCCCACCCCCAGCGGGGUCAUCUCCCCAAGCAGCACCAUCCACAUACCACUGGUCCUGGAGACCCAGGUCACUGGAGAACACAGAUCCACGGUUUACAUCUCAAUCUUUGGGAGCCAGGACCCCCCUUUGGUAUGUCACUUAAAGAGCGCUGGAGAAGGCCCAGUUAUCUACGUCCAUCCCAAUCAAGUGGACUUCGGGAAUAUCUACGUCCUAAAAGACUCUUCCAGGAUUCUCAACCUAUGCAACCAGUCCUUCAUUCCCGCAUUUUUCCAGGCACACAUGGCACACAAAAAAUCCCUUUGGACGAUUGAACCCAAUGAAGGCAUGGUUCCUCCAGAAACUGAUGUUCAACUGGCACUGACCGCCAACCUGAAUGACACACUGACAUUCAAGGACUGUGUUAUUUUGGACAUUGAAAAUAGCAGUACCUAUCGGAUUCCUGUUCAGGCUUCCGGAACUGGUUCCACUAUUGUUUCAGAUAAGCCCUUUGCUCCAGAACUCAAUUUGGGGGCACAUUUUAGCCUGGAUACCCACUAUUACCACUUUAAGUUGAUCAACAAGGGACGUCGGAUCCAACAGUUGUUCUGGAUGAAUGAUAGCUUCCGACCCCAGGCCAAGCUGAGUAAGAAGGGCCGGGUUAAGAAGGGACAUGCUCAUGUCCAACCCCAGCCCAGUGGCUCUCAGGAGCCCAGGGAUCCACAGAGCCCCGUGUUUCAUCUCCACCCCGCCAGCAUGGAGCUGUACCCAGGCCAGGCAAUUGAUGUGAUACUCGAAGGCUAUUCUGCUACUCCCAGGAUAGUGAAAGAGAAGCUGGUGUGCCACGCCAUCAUCGGGGCACAGAAGGGGAAGAGCUUGGUGAUGGCUGUGAACAUCACCUGUGAGUUCGUCGCACCUCUCAUCCAGCUCUCCACCAAGCAGCUCAUCUACCGACUGGAGAAGAAACCUAACAGUAUCCUGAAACCUGAUUACCAGCCCUUGGCCAUAAAGAACAUUUCCACCCUGCCCGUGAACUUGUUGCUGUCAACAUCUGGACCCUUCUUUAUAUGUGAGACUGAUAAAUCCCUGCUGCCGGCAACUCCUGAGCCUAUUAAACUGGAAAUUGAUGAAGAAAAAAACCUGCUGAUCAAGUUUGACCCUUCCUACAGAAACGAUCUGAACAACUGGGUGGCAGAAGAAAUUCUAGCAAUUAAGUAUGUGGAACACCCUCAGAUAGACAGCCUGGACCUGCGCGGAGAAGUGCAUUACCCCAACCUCAGCUUUGAGACAAAGGAGCUGGAUUUUGGCUGCAUCCUGAACGAUACUGAGCUCAUUCGCUACGUUACCAUCACCAACUGCAGUCCGUUGGUUGUGAAGUUUCGCUGGUUCUUCUUGGUGAAUGAUGAGGAAAAUCAGAUAAGGUUUGUGACAUUGCCGAAGAAGCCCUACAGUGCCCCAGUGUCCCAGAUGGAGUCCAUCCCAGCAACCUCAGAGGCUGCCAGCCCACCAGCAAUCCUAGUUACAGUAGAGUCCCCCGAGAUGGAUUUAAAUGAUUUUGUUAAGACUGUCCUUGUGGAUGAAGAUGCCAGGCCUGAAGAAAAAGAACUAAGAAAAACGAAAGCUUCCAGUGUGAUCUCAGAUGAAAUAAAAAUUAGCUCUACUGAAAUAGAAAGAAUAUACUCAAGCCAGAGCCAGGUGGAGGAUCAGGAAUCCCUACAGACCUGUGAACAGAAUGAGAUGCUUUCCAUUGGGAUAGAAGAAGUGUUUGAUAUUUUGCCCCUGUUUGGAGUGUUGCAGCCACACAGUAGCCACCAAAUAUCGUUCACCUUCUAUGGACACGCUAACAUCAUUGCACAAGCUAAAGCUCUGUGUGAAGUGGAAGAAGGACCCACCUACGAAAUAACACUGAAGGGAGAGGCGUCCCUGGUCAACUAUUCCUUUGACACCAAGGAUAUUCACUACGGAUUACAGCUGUUUGACCAUGUCACAGAGAGGGAAAUCACGCUGACGAACAUGGGGAAAGUUGGCUUUGAGUUCAAGGUUCUGACUGACCACCAGUCUUCUCCAGACAACCUUCUCCCUGGAGUGCCACUAAUCCUGCCUGUGUCUGGCUUUAUCAGUUCACAUCAAGAGCAGGUAUUAAAAGUUUACUACCUACCUGGAGUACCUGAGGUCUUUAAAAGGAGUUUCCAGAUACAGAUCGCCCACCUGGACCCAGAAAAUAUCACUCUGAGCGGAGAGGGAAUCUUUCCCCAAAUCUGCCUCGAUCUCCCCAGGAACCUCACAGCAAAUGAAAAGUAUGAAAUGUUCUUGAAUCAAGCCAGGAAAAACACAGACAAAGAGUAUAACAAAUGUGAAAUGCUCGAUCACUUUGACAUAAUAACUGAGGAAGUGCCAGAAGACGAGCCUGCUGAGGUAAGUGCUCAUCUCCAGAUGGAGGUAGAAAGACUUAUAGUCCAAAGCUAUGUCCUAGAACAUCAGAAAACAACCACCCCUGAUCCUAUGGAUGACCCCUGCUUCAGCCAUCGGAGUCGCCGCAAACUGGCCAAAAUCCAGCUACCAGAGUACAUCCUGGACUUUGGCUACAUCAUCCUUGGCGAAGUCCGAACCCACAUCAUCAAGAUCAUCAACACCAGUCACUUUCCAGUGUCAUUCCAUGCAGACAAGCGUGUCCUUCAUGAGACAGGAUUCAGUACUGAGCUAGAUCGUGUAAAGAAUCUACCUCAUUGUGAAACGGAAAUAUUUGAAGUGAGAUUUGACCCACAGGGGGCCAAUCUUCCUGUUGGAAGCAAAGAAGUCAUUCUGCCCAUCAAGGUGGUUGGAGGGCCAACAGUUCACAUCUGUCUCCAAGCCAAGGUGACCAUUCCAACCAUGACUCUCUCUCGUGGAAAAGUGGACUUUGCCACAAUUCAGUGUGGACAGUGCCUGGUGGAAACUAUUCAGCUUUCCAAUCAUCUCCAAGUCCCUUGUGAAUGGUUCGUCCAGAGCCAAAAGCCUGUUGACAAGCUGGAGAAACACAUGCCGAAGUACUUAAGACAGAAACUACGCGCUGAAUUAAAGCCAAAGACACGGAUCUUCGAAAUCCAGCCCAUUUCUGGAGUCUUGGAUCCUGGUGAGAAGUCCAACGUGCAAGUGAAAUUCAUGCCAAAAGAAGAGAAAUUCUACAGCCAAACCCUGGUGUUUCAGAUUGCCCAGAGUGCUCAAAAGCUUACCCUCCUGGCACGUGGGCAAGGUCUAGAGCCACGCCUGGAAUUUAGUCCUUCAGUCCUGGAUCUGGGGCCACUGCUACUUUGUGCACCUGGAGACGAGGCCGAGGUGAUAGUGAAGAAUCCCUGCAACUUCCCCAUUGAGUUUUAUUCCUUAGAAUUUGAUCAGCAGUAUCUCAUAGAAGAAAAGAUCUUGCGGAAGCUGAAGGGCUAUGAUUCCUACAACACCCUGCUGCUGCCUCCCCGCAACCCUGGGGAGAAGCUGCCCCCAGAACUGUACGAGUACUUCAAAGAGAUAAAGAAGUCAAAAGAGGAGCAGAUGAGGGCGAAAUAUCUGGAGAAUCUGGCACAGGAGAAUGAAGAGGAAGAUAUAACCUCAUCAGAUCAGGGAACCUCCAAUAGCACAAAGAGGACAUCGCUGAGCCGAGGGAUCUCUGUCACAUCCAACCUGGAAGAAUGGCACGCCCUGUUGGUCGAGUCCAAAACCUACCUAGAGGAAGAGGAGGAUGAGGAAAGCCUGGAAAAAAUCAUUUUCCAAACUGACAAGCUUCAGAGCAUUGACAGCCACUCCAUGGAGGAAGUUGGAGAGGUGGAAAACAACCCAGUGAGCAAAGCAAUCGCUCGCCACCUGGGCAUUGACAUUUCUGCAGAAGGCCGCCUGGCCAAGAACCGGAAAGGCAUCGCCAUUAUCAUUCAUGGGACACCCUUGUCAGGAAAGUCAGCCAAUGCCGUUAGCGUGGCCAAGUACUACAACGCAGCCUGCCUGAGCAUCGACUCCAUUGUGCUGGAAGCUGUGGCCAACAGCAACAACAUCCCAGGGAUCCGGGCCCGUGAGCUCUGCAUCAGGGCUGCCAUAGAGCAGUCCGUGAAGGAAGGAGAGGAGGCUGCCCAGGAGGCAGCUGUGGGUCAAAACGUCAUAGGGCAAGGACGACUGAGCACUGACACCUUGGGCAAGUUAGCCUCCGAGAUGACUCUGGUGGCCCCAGAAAUUAAACCUGGAAAGAGUGUUCGUGGGAGCGUGGUGAUCACCAAAAGCAAGGCAGACAGCCAUGGCUCCGGGUCACAGAAGCAGCAUCACUCACACCAGUCUGAAACACCACAGAUUUCCUCCAGCCCUCUCCCCCCGGGGCCCAUCCACCGCUGGCUCAGUGUUAGUCCCAGUGUCGGAGGCGAGACCGGGCUGAUGAGCUGUGUGCUCCCGGAUGAACUUCUCGUGCAGAUCCUGGCAGAGCGGAUACAGCUGAGUGACUGCUACCGAGGAGUGGUGUUUGAUGGCCUCGACACUCUCUUUGCUCAGAAUGCUGCAGCCGCCCUCCUCUGCCUGCUGAAGGCCAUUGGCAGCCGGGAGCAUAUAUACAUUCUCAACAUGGCCCAGGAUUACGCAGCCAUGAAGGCCCAGGAGAAAGCCAAAAAGGAGCAAGAAGAACGCAAGCACAAGGGAGCUCUUGAGAAAGAGAAGGAGCGUCUCCAAAACAUGGAUGAGGAAGAAUAUGAUGCCCUGACUGAGGAGGAGAAACUCACAUUCGAUCGGGGGAUUCAGCAGGCGCUCCGCGAGCGGAAGAAGAGGGAGCAGGAGAGGCUGGCAAAGGAAAUGCAAGAAAAGAAGCUACAGCAGGAGCUGGAGCGACAAAAGGAAGAGGAUGAGCUGAAACGGAGGGUCAAAAAAGGAAAGCAGGGACCCAUUAAGGAGGAGCCCCCCAUGAAGAAAUCUCAAGCAGCAAACAAGCAGGUUCCUCCGCUCACCAAAGUGGAUGUCAAGAUGGAGACAAUCGAAAGGAAAAUAUCUGUUAGGGAACAAACAAUGUCUGAGAAGGAAGAGCUAAAUAAGAAGAAAAGGAACAUGGGCGAUGUCAGCAUGCAUGGGCUUCCUCUUGUCCAGGACCAAGAGGACAGUGAAGGGGACAACUCAAAGGACCCCGACAAGCAACUGGCCCCGAAGUUUAAGACCUAUGAAUUGACACUGAAGGAUGUCCAGAACAUCCUCAUGUACUGGGACCGGAAGCAAGGAGUCCAGCUGCCUCCUGCAGGGAUGGAGGAAGCGCCCCAUGAGCCCGACGACCAGCGCCAGGUCCCCUUGGGUGGGCGCAGGGGCCGCAAGGACCGGGAGAGAGAGCGCCUGGAGAAGGAGCGCACGGAGAAGGAGCGCCUGGAGAGGGAGAAGGCGGAGCGGGAGCGCCUGGAGAAGCUGCGAGCCCUGGAGGAGCGGAGCGACUGGGAGGGGGAAGGGGAGGAGGACCACGAAGGGAAGAAGGAGAAGGACCUGGGCGUACCCUUCCUAGACAUCCAGACACCAGACUUUGAAGGCUUGAGCUGGAAGCAGGCCCUAGAGAGCGACAAGCUUCCCAAAGGAGAGCAGAUCCUAGACAUCUUGGGUCUGGGUGCCUCCGGACCACCCAUCCCGCCUCCCGCCUUAUUCUCAAUCGUCUCCUACCCGGUGAAGCGGCCACCUUUGACCAUGACAGACGACCUGGAGCAUUUUGUAUUUGUGAUCCCACCAUCCGAAGAUAUAUCUCUGGAUGAAAAAAAAGAAAUGGAAAUAGAAUCAGACUUUUUGGCCACCACAAACACUACAAAGGCUCAAGAGGAGCAGACCAGCUCAUCUAAGGGGGGCAAACAGAAAAUGAAAGAAAAGAUAGACCAAGUCUUCGAGAUUCAGAAAGACAAGCGUCACAUGGCCUUAAACAGGAAGGUCCUUUCUGGGGAACCUGCUGGAACCAUUUCCCAGCUGUCAGAUACAGACCUGGACAACUUCAACGGGCAGCACUCCCAGGAGAAAUUCACCAGACUGAAUCACUUCCGGUGGAUCGUGCCAGCCAAUGGCGAGGUAACGUUGCAGGUGCACUUCUCUUCUGAUGAGUUCGGGAACUUUGACCAAACCUUUAACUUUGAGAUCCUAGGAACUUGCUGCCAGUACCAGCUCUACUGCCGAGGCAUCUGCACUUACCCAUACAUUUGCCAAGACCCAAAAGUGGUAUUUCCUCAGCGGAAGAUGGACAUGAAGACAAAUGAGGUCAUCUUUAAGAAGUAUGUUAUGAGCACGGAGACGUACUACUUUGGGCCACUACUUUGUGGAAAAUCAAGAGAUAAGUACAAGUCAUCCUUAUUCCCAGGCAACAUGGAGACGCUAACAAUCCUGAACACUUCCUUAAUGGUGGUGGAGGCAUCCUUCUAUUUUCAGAAUGAUGUCAAAGCAAACACGUACUUCCUGGAACCCAACACCAUGGUCCUGAAACCCAAUGAGAAGCAGAUAUUAAACGUAUGGGCCUACCCUACUUCAGUUGGUGUCUUUGAAGACAGCAUUGUCUGCUGCAUCAAUGACAACCCAGAGCCAGCCAUCUUCCAAUUAAGCUGCCAGGGGAUCCGCCCGGAACUAGAGCUGGAACCCAGGCAAUUACAUUUUGACCGGCUCUUGCUGCACAGACAGGAAUCCAGGGUAGUUCUUCUCCGCAAUGUCACGCUCCUGCCUGUGGCCUGGCGGAUCACCAGCCUGGAGCACUUGGGUGAUGAUUUCACUGUAUCCCUGAUGCAGGGGACCAUCCCCCCUGAGGCUGAGUACGGCCUGCACCUGUACUUUCAGCCCACCAAGCCUGUCAACAUCAAGAAGGCUAUUCGGUUGGAGGUUUUAGAUGCAGAAAAUCUUCUUGGUGUUGUUCAGAUUGAAAAUAUCAUGGUCUUUGCAGAGGCAUACGACAUCGCCUUGGACAUCACCUUCCCCAAAGGAGCUGAAGGGGGACUGGAUUUUGGGAUUGUCAGGGUCACAGAGGAGGCGAAGCAGCCCCUGCAAUUGAAGAACCGUGGGAAAUAUGAGAUCGCGUUCAGCUUUUCCGUGGACUCUGUAGGGAUUUCAACACCUAAUAUAAAUUCCAUGAUCUCAGUCCAACCCAAAAAGGGUUCACUGACCCCAACAGAAAAACCCACAAAUGUCCAAGUUUUCUUCCAUGCAAAAAAGGAAGUGAAGAUUGAGCACCAGCCUGUUCUGCGCUGUCAGAUUAUUGAGCCCAAUAUUUCAGAAGGAGGUGAGAUCAUUGCCAGCAUCCCAAUUAAGUUUUCCGCGAAUGCAGUAUAUUCCAAAUACAACAUCACCCCCUCCUCUGUCAUCAACUUUGGAGCUUUGAUCUGUGGCACUCGUAAAAGCACCACCUUCACCAUAGAAAAUCAAGGUGUUACUGACUUCAAGUUCGCCCUUUAUAAGCUGACAGGGGAGAGCCCCAUUCAUCAAAAGAAAGCAGCCAGCCACGUCAGACAUGCAAGAUCCCGAGAAAGUGAGAGCUUCUACAAAACUGGCUCUUCCAGAGCAGCCAAGUUCUCUGACACGAUUCAGAAAGAAGUAACCACCACAGGCCAGGCCCGCUUCGCCCAUGGCAUGUUCACCGUGUACCCUGGGUUUGGCUCCAUUCCUUCCGGAGGACAGCAGGUCAUCAACGUUGACUGUGUGGCUGACGCCAUGGGAAAGUGUGAGGAGUUUAUAGCCAUCGAUAUCUCCGGCCGAGACCCUGCAGUCCACCCUGCCGGCAUUCUUUACACUUUGCUAGCUGAAGCCUGUCUACCAGCCUUCGUGACCGAAAACAAUGCCUUGAUAUUUGAAGAGCACCAGAUAUGUACCAGUGCCAACCUGCACCACAUCCUGCAGACCAUAGAGAGCGGGGGGCUGUUCGUCGAGGAUGAGAACAAGUUCAUCUUCUGCAAUGUCCUGGUGGGCCGCCAAGCCAAGGCUCGUUUCAAGAUCAGCAACGUGGGAAAGAUCACCUGUGAUGUCAACAUUGUAGUCAGGCCUAUCUCCAAUAAGCCCUUUGCCCGCAUCGUCGACAUUUUUGAAGUGGAACCCAGCAAGAUGUGCAUUGCCAGUCAUUCCCAUGCCUUUGCCACGGUGUCCUUCACCCCGCAGAUCAUGCAGAACUACCAGUGCAUCUUUGAGGCUACCUUGGAUGGCUUGCCCAGCACCCUGGCCAAGAGCCGAGGCCUCGUGUUUGACAUCGCUGGUGAGGGGAACCUCCCUCGAGUGACGGUUGUGCGGCCAGUUCUUCAUAACCAAUAUGGAAACCCCUUGCUCCUCUUUAAGAGGCUUCUCCUUGGUCAUUCAGAGAAGCUGCCUCUCAUCCUCAAGAACAAUGGUGUCCUCCCUGCCCAGCUGCAUGUUGACCUGCAGGAUGAGCUAGGAGUCUUCUCCCUGAAAGGGAGGCCCACCACCGCGUAUAUCUACAUCACAGAGGAAAAUAAACCACAUGUAAAAGCAAAGAAAGCUCACACAGCCUCCUUGGUUGUUUCUCCUGGAGAUACAGCUGAAUUUGAUGUCGUUUUCCACUCCCAGAAGGUUGGGAGGAUGAGAGGUAUCAUCCACUUGUCAGUGAUCAACAACCAAUAUGAGGAGACCUCCAUCCACAUGGUGGGAGAGGGCUAUGAGGAUGACAUCACCUUGGACAACAUCCAUGGACUGGUGGCCCCCACCAGCCAGGAAGACAUAAGUAUCUCUGAGUUCACAGAGAUCAUCGAGGACAAUGAUAUGGAAGACUUGGUGGCAGCUGCUCUGGUGGACCACAUCCAAUUUGGGGACUGCCACAUUGGACACAGCUAUAAUGCGAGCUUCACAGUCACAAAUCACAGCCAAGUGAACUUGAUACGGUUUGAAUGGCCUGUUUCAGCUACAAUUGCUUUCUCCCCACAGAUGGGCCACCUCCACCCUGGGUGUGCCAAGGACAUAGUGGUGACCAUGAAGUCAGAUGUACCCAUCAACCUAAAGAAUAUGCGGAUCAGGUGCAAGCUCUCCAGGAUUAUGUUUCAGCUCCCUGCAGACCAGGUCCCCGACUGGGAUGACCGCAUGCACACAGUCAAGUGGGUGGACGUACCCAGAAACAUGCCUGGGACUUUCACUACAAAACGAAAAGUGAUAGAGACGGAUCCGGAACCUGCUCACUCAGUACUAGAAGAAAACUACCAAGAACUGCAGCUUCAAAUCAGUGCCAAUGUGGAUUUCGCUUCAUACCAUUGCCAAGCAAGAGAUGUGCGCUUUAAGGAAACCUUGGUUUACCAGACCCGAGUGUUUGAGUUCGAUGUGAUUAAUUCAGGACGUGUCCAGCUGGAAUUCAGCUGGGUCUCAGAAGAUACCUCAAAGGCAGUCAGCUUUGCAAAACCAGAUCACCAAGGUUCAGCUCAAAAAGAUCAGCUUAGUCAGGGCACGAUGCAUACAGGCAGCACCCUGGACAGCACCAUGGACCACUGGGCCGAGGGUUCCCCACAGCCCUUCUCUGUGGAGCCCUCUUCGGGAAUCGUGCCGGUGGGGAAGAUUCAGAAGUUCAAAGUAAAAUUCUCCCCGUUGGACAUUGGAGACUUCGAGAGCAACCUUUUCUGCCAGAUUCCCAACCUGCCACCUGGAGAGCAAGGUCCGGUCCUGGUAGCAAAAGGGCGGAGCACCUUGCCCAUCUGCCAUUUUGAUCUGAAAGACUCGGACUACAUAAGUGGCCAUCAGCGCAACCCAGAGCUCCGAGGGUCCAGUGGGGGAGCUCUGGAUCCAAACACCCGGGUGAUUGAGUUCACCACUGUGGGCAUAGGAGGGAAGAAUCUCCGGACCUUUACCAUCCUAAACCCAACCAAUAGCACCUACUCCUUCUGCUGGAUCUCUGAAGAAAUUGAAAGUCUCCAGAACCCUGCAGCAUUCACAUGCCUUACAGAAAAGGGCUUCAUCCACCCUGAAAAGAAAGCCGAGAUCGUGUUCCAGUUCACACCUUUCCAUCUGGGCAUCACUGAGUCAUCAUGGACCUUCCUAAUUCCCGAGCACAACAUCACAGUCCCUUUCCUGCUGGUAGGCAAAACUACCGAACCUCUCAUCUCUCUGAACAAGUCACACCUCAACUUCAGCUCUCUCCUCAUUGGCAGAGAAGCCAGGGAGACUGUGCAGAUCAUUAACAAGGAGGAGCAGGGGUUCGAUUUUUCCUUCCAGGACAACUCCCGCUAUUCUGAAGGUUUCAGCAACAGCCUGCUUGUAUGUCCCAUGGAAGGCUGGAUCCCACCACUGUCCAGGUUCCCAAUUGAUAUUUUCUUCACACCAAAGCAGGAAGGAGAUGUGAACUUUAAUUUGAUCUGCAAUGUGGAAAAGAAAGUCCACCCUGUGACAUUAAAUGUCAAGGCCGAGGGCUACACUAUGAAUGUGGAGAUCAAGUGCAAGGACAGGACAGGCUCCAUCACUCUGUUGACUCCCAACCAGACUAACAUCAUCAACUUCUAUGAGGUGGAGUUAAAUGAAUGUGUCCAGUGUGAAUUCAACUUUAUCAACACUGGAAAGUUCACCUUCAGCUUCCAGGCACAGCUGUGUGGCUCCAAAACCUUGCUGCAGUACUUGGAAUUUUCACCCAUCGACAGCACUGUGGAUGUAGGACAGAGUGUACAUGCCACCCUGUCUUUUCAACCAUUAAAGAAGUGUGUCUUGACAGACCUGGAACUCAUAAUCAAGAUCAGCCAUGGUCCAACAUUUAUGUGCAACAUCUCAGGCUGUGCUGUGAGCCCGGCUAUCCAUUUCUCCUUCACCAGCUACAACUUUGGGACCUGCUUUAUCUAUCAAGCUGGGAUGCCCCCAUACAAACAAACCCUGGUAAUUACCAACAAGGAAGAAACACCUAUGAGCAUAGAUUGUCUGUACACCAACACCACUCACCUCGAGGUGAACUCCCGUGUUGAUGUGGUAAAGCCAGGAAACACAUUGGAGAUUCCAAUAACUUUUUAUCCUCGAGAAAGUAUCAACUAUCAAGAACUCAUUCCCUUUGAAAUCAAUGGGCUCUCACAACAAACAGUCGAAAUCAAAGGGAAGGGUACCAAAAUGAAGAUUUUAGUCCUAGAUCCAGCCAACAGGAUUGUGAAGUUGGGAGCUGUCCUACCAGGGCAGGUUGUGAAAAGAACAGUUUCCAUCAUGAACAACAGCCUGGCCCAGCUCACAUUUAAUCAGUCCAUUCUGUUCACAAUUCCAGAACUCCAGGAACCCAAGGUCCUUACCCUGGCGCCCUUCCACAACAUCACACUGAAGCCCAAAGAAGUCUGUAAACUGGAAGUCAUCUUUGCCCCGAAGAAGCGUGUCCCUCCCUUCUCUGAGGAAGUGUUCAUGGAAUGCAUGGGGCUCCUGCGCCCCCUCUUCCUCCUUAGCGGCUGCUGCCAGGCCCUGGAGAUCUCACUGGACCAGGAACAUAUUCCCUUUGGACCCGUGGUGUAUCAGACGCAAGCCACACGUCGCAUCCUCAUGAUGAACACAGGCGAUGUGGGUGCAAGGUUUAAAUGGGACAUCAAAAAAUUUGAGCCUCAUUUCUCCAUUAGCCCAGAAGAAGGCUAUAUUACCUCAGGCAUGGAGGUUUCUUUUGAAGUGACCUACCAUCCCACCGAGGUGGGAAAGGAGAGCCUUUGUAAAAACAUUCUCUGCUACAUCCAGGGAGGCAGUCCUCUGAGUCUAACCCUGUCUGGAGUCUGCGUGGGACCACCUGCGGUAAAAGAGGUAGUGAAUUUCACGUGCCAGGUGCGCUCCAAGCACACGCAGACCAUCCUGCUGUCAAACCGCACCAACCAGACCUGGAAUCUGCACCCCAUCUUUGAGGGCGAGCACUGGGAGGGGCCUGAGUUCAUCACCCUGGAGGCCCACCAGCAAAACAAGCCCUAUGAGAUCACCUACAGGCCCCGCACCAUGAACUUGGAGAACCGCAAGCACCAGGGCACCCUCUUCUUCCCCCUCCCAGAUGGGACCGGCUGGCUGUAUGCUCUGCAUGGGACUUCUGAGCUCCCCAAAGCUGUAGCCAAUAUCUAUCGUGAAGUGCCAUGUAAGACCCCCUACACUGAGCUUCUGCCAAUCACCAACUGGCUGAACAAGCCCCAGAGAUUCCGGGUCAUCGUGGAAAUACUGAAACCAGAGAAGCCGGACCUAAGCAUCACUAUGAAGGGCCUUGAUUACAUUGAUGUACUGUCUGGCUCUAAGAAAGACUACAAGCUGAACUUCUUUUCCCACAAGGAGGGAACGUACGCUGCAAAGGUGAUCUUCCGAAACGAGGUGACAAAUGAGUUCUUGUACUACAAUGUGAGUUUCAGGGUCAUCCCUUCAGGCAUCAUCAAAACCAUCGAGAUGGUGACCCCAGUCCGGCAAGUUGCGUCAGCCUCCAUCAAGUUGGAGAACCCUCUGCCCUACUCGGUGACCUUCUCCACGGAAUGCCGGAUGCCCGACAUCGCCCUGCCCUCCCAGUUUGUGGUGCCUGCCAACUCCGAGGGCACGUUCUCAUUUGAAUUUCAGCCCCUGAAAGCUGGAGAAACCUUCGGAAGACUAACUUUGCACAACACUGACUUGGGUUACUACCAAUAUGAGCUCUAUCUGAAAGCCACGCCAGCACUUCCGGAAAAGCCUGUUCACUUCCAGACUGUCCUUGGCAGCAGCCAAAUCAUCCUUGUGAAGUUCAUCAAUUACACACGGCAGAGGACAGAAUACUACUGCAGGACCGACUGUACAGACUUCCACGCAGAAAAACUCAUUAAUGCAGCCCCAGGAGGCCAGGGAGGCACUGAAGCCAGUGUGGAAGUCUUAUUCGAGCCCAGCCACCUGGGUGAGACCAAGGGCAUCCUGAUCCUAUCAUCGCUCGCAGGUGGAGAGUAUAUCAUCCCCCUCUUUGGAAUGGCUCUGCCUCCCAAGCCCCAAGGUCCCUUCUCGAUCCGAGCCGGGUACAGCAUAAUCAUCCCCUUCAAGAAUGUCUUCUAUCACAUGGUGACCUUCUCCAUCAUCGUGGAUAACCCAGCCUUCACCAUUCGCGCUGGAGAGUCUGUGCGGCCCAAGAAGAUCAACAACAUCACAGUCUCCUUUGAAGGAAACCCAUCUGGCAGCAAAACCCCCAUCACCACCAAGCUGACUGUGAGCUGCCCUCCUGGUGAAGGGAGUGAGACUGGAGUUAAAUGGGUUUAUUAUCUGAAGGGGAUCACCCUUUAGUGGUAACCAGGGUUACCUGUAUCAACCAAAAGCUAUGCAUUGUCUUAGCCUGAAAAAGAAUAGAGAAAACAAUAAGAAUUCUAAAGGAACUGUUUUUAUUCUUCUCAUACAAUUAUAGGGCAGUUAUUUCCCUAUUAUGUGUUUUCCAAAUAUAGAUAUGAAAUAUCUAUUCCAUAUUAAACAUUAUAACUACACACAACAGCUCUAUAUUUUAGACAACUGAAUCCUUGUGAGUCCCUAAAUUGAGUUUCUUGACAUAGCCCCAAAGCUCAAGUACUUUGUAAUAAUUCCCAUUUUUAUCAAGAAGGCACAGGUAUCACACUAGUGACCUUCUACUCUACAACACUUAGCAAUGCGUGACGCUGGGUACUGCAGUUUCUUUUUAAAAUCCAAAAUGGUUUAAAAAGCCCUUAGACAUGACUAUUUUGAUGUGGCAUUUUAUUCUGCUUUCACAUAAAAGCCAAAUAAAUAUUUUCAGAGGGAUGAGCAGAUAACAUUAGGGCAAUCCAGGGACACUCCCAUCACUUUUUCUCUUGGCUUUUAUACCAUCAGUGUCCGAAUCCCACAUCUGCCCUACACAGAAAGUUCUCACUGAAGUCUAGGCCCUGGAGAAAGGCUAAUAGAGAUCCCAGCUCCCCCCACCACACAUACACACCCCGCCUUGGAUAGCAUUCAGCAGGAGAGCAGGGAUUCUCAACCCAUCUGCACAUCAGGACCACCUAACUCUCACUCUGAACGUGCCCAGUCCCCAUCUGAUGUAAUUGGUCUGGAGAGGGGUGUGGGCAUCUUUAUUAUAUACAUUUAACUUGUAUAGCAGAUGGUUAAAGUCUGGCCCUGGCAUGGGUUUGCUUCUGCAGACAUACACCUCUGACGGAGGGUCCCCCUGCCUCUACCUGCUCCCCACACUCAUCCCCCACAGCCCUCCUACAAGAGGGGCAGGAGACUGGAAGAAGAUGGCCUCUUGGGAAUGAAUGCCGUAAAGAAGUGGGUCUUAAAAAUGGUCCCUGGGCCAGCAGCAGUACUAUCACCUGGGAAUUUAUUAAAAGUCAAACUCUCAGUCCCCAUGUCAGAUCGACUGAAUCAAAAAGUCUGUAGGUGUGGCCCGGCAAUCUUUUAGCAAGUCCUUAUACCUGUCAGAGGUGGCUUUCAUGGAGGGAGACUCUUCUCCUUCUUCUGUACCUCCCCACAACCCUAGCCCAGUAUACUCUAGGACCAAAAAAGCUUUUUCUAGAAUGUCUGUAAACACAGACCUUUACAAUAGUCCUCCCUCAUCCUCAGGGGAUACAUUCCAAGGUGCCCAGUAGAUGCCUGAAACCACAGAUAGUACUGAACACUCCAUAUACUGUGGUAUUUUCCUUUACAUACAUACCUUUGAUUAAUUUAUAAAUUAGGCACAGUAAGACAUUAACAAUAAUAAUAAUAAAAUGUAAUAAUUAUAAUAAUAUGCCAGCAUCACUACCCAUGUGCUUUGGGGCCAUUAUUAAACUAAAUAAGGUUUCCUUGAACACAAGCAUUGCGAUCCCAUGACAGUUGACCUGCUAACCCCAAGUCAUCUACUCAGUGACUAUCAAGUAGGUUGUGUCUACAGCAUGCAUACGCUAGACGAGGGGAUGAUUCACAUCCUGAGCAGGAUGGAGUGGGAUGGCAUGAGAUUUCCUCAAGUUAUUCAGAACAGCAUGCCAUUUAAAAAGUAUGAAUUUUUUAUUUCUGGAAUUUUUCAUUAAAUAUUUUCAUUCCACAGUUGACCACAGGUAACUGAAGCCAUAGAUGAGGAGGACUGCCAUACUCAAUAGACAAUUUAUUUCUAUAACCUCUAAAGACACUACUGAUAGGUCUAAAGACAACCAGAUGACAGAUUUUCACAAUGGUUAAGUGAGCAAAGAUCGCUCUGACCAAUAAUCUGAGAGGAUGCUAAGAUCAAUGAGCAAGAGUGAUGACUUGCAAAUAUACAGCAUCUGUAUAAAGUCAGUGCUUCUGAAAUAUUAGUAUACAUCAGCAUCCCCUGGAGGGCUUACUGAAACAGAUUGCUGAGCCCCACCCUCAGGAAGUCCGAUCUAGGAGAUUUGGGUGGGGCUUGAGAAUCUGCAUUUCUAACCAGUUCUUGGUGAUGCUCGUUGGUGAGACCAAUCAGACUGUGAGAACCACGACUCUAAAGCCUCGAGCCUCCUGGUUAUUCGGAGUGGCCUAUGGACCUGCAGCAUCAGCAUCACCUGGGAAUUUGUUAGAAAGGCAGGCCCUCAGGCCCCACCCUAGACUUGUUGAAUCAGAAUCUGCAUUUUCAUGGACCUCCAGGCGAUUUGCAUGCACAUUGCAGCUGAGAGUGCUACUUUAAGGUACCUGGCAAAACUUGACAUUUGCCAAACCCACAGCCAUAACUCUUUCAUUACAGUCCUGAGAAGUCUUACCAAAUCUGCAUAGGACCUAGUUGAUGAAAUUAACCCUCCCCAAAAUGUGCCUCCUUCCACCUAUUCACCAGAGGUAUAGGUUAGGAGAAGGGAAGCAAUUGGUCCCUCACCCUACUCUUCAAAAGGGUGUACUUUUUCAAUAAUGGUCAAUGUGGUACACCAAGUGAUCCCUAAGACUAAAGAAAAGGUGGAAGAAGCUGUCUGAAAUCUUGUCUAACAUGCCACCAGCCCCAGCAUGGCUUAUAGCCAGCCUUGGGGUGGCUAGGGGCAACUCCCCCAACUUCAGACCUGUUCCAGUGCUUCCCCAAGCCACUGAAGCUGUCCAUAUACAUUUUAUAAAAGUGAUCAGGGAGAAGGGAGGGGGAGAAACAAAAACGAACCCAGGUUGCAGCACACUCAGCAUUAAUCACUAGAUCAGCCUGCGCUCAGACCUGCUUCCUCAUAGCUGUUUGGUGCCUGCUGUUUCAGAAUCACGUAGACCCUGCUAAAGAUCAUAGUUCCCCUCAAUGCUCUGGAGAUAACAACUUGAACAUUAGGAAACGUUAAGUUUUCCGUUUGAGAUAUUUAUUCUUGGUCCUGUGUACCAGUGAAACAACUGACAUCAGCUGAUCUGAAGGACCUCACGAGAAGCUGAUUCACCAAAGAAUGCGGUUUCCACAUCCUGAUGAUUUCAUCCGUCUUACCCAACCAAUCAGUCACCUGGUUUUUCAGCCCUUCACCCUCCAGGAUCCCCUUAAAAACCCCAGUCCAGAACUCUUCCGGGAGAUGGAUUUGAGGGUCUCCUCCCAUCUCAUCACUCAGUGACCUUUGAUCAUCACUUUCUCUGCUGCAUCCCCACUGUCUCUGUGCAUUGGUCUGUUACUGCACAGUGGGCACACAAACGUGUUGGUCCUAUAACACCACUGAGUCUAGGGUCCAAAUCCUCCUAGCCCCUGAGAGAGGAGGAAGUUCCUUCUCCCUGGGACCAAGAGCCAAGCUCAGAUCCUGCCCCAGUGUGAACCCUCUUCCAGGCUGGUUUGAGAUUGGGUGCAUUUCUUCCCUUUAGGUUUUUCUCGUGCUUCCUUAGCCUCAAACAAUAACAAAAUAGUCUUAUAUUAGCAAAUUUGGAAUGGCAAAGUAGCUUAACAGCAGGCUUGAUGAAAAUAACCCUUCCAACACAUGCUUGUGGAAGUUACAUUGGAGAAUCCAUUCUCAGCAAAGCAGACCAGGAGACUUCUAACUGGGGGAUGUUCAGAAAAUGUCAGGGUAGCUGUGUGGCAGAACUCCAAGGAGCACUGUGCACAGAAUACCAUGGGAAUGGGGCUCCCUGGCCUCGUUCCACACUGGGCCCCCAGUGAGUGUGGCAUGCUAAGUCUAACCACUUCUUUAGGAGCCUCAAGUCAGAGGUGACAAUACUGUAACAUUGGUGAGGGCCUGCUACAUUUCAAGACCUCUACCUAAUACCUUAAACCCUGUUGCCCUGAAACUCCAGCUACAAUUACAUUGCUGUUGGAGAAACUGCUUUGCACAGUUCAAGAUUUUGGUACAAUUUCUUACAAUGUCAUCAGCAGCCUCUUGCUACAAGUUAUGUCAUAACUUUUACAUACUUGUAAUAGCUAUUAUGAAUAGUUGUUACAGAACUAUUACAAGUUCUAGCAUAACAACCAAGCAUCACACAGAUGCAGAUGAAUUGUAACUGUGAAAUAAUGACUAGUAUGCAGUCAGGCACAUCAGUUAUCCCCUAGUCUAGAAGAGUUUCAACAGGAAUGGUCACAGGUCAGAGAAGAGGAACAAGGGUGGAAGGCAAGGGUAGCCUUUGGGCUUUAUUUUUACCACCACUGCUAGCUCAAUUAUGCAUAAAUAAUCUUACCUAGUUGGCAUUUUUCAAGAUAUUAGAGAAAAGAACCACUUCUUUCUAGGAACUUCUGACCUAAAGGUAGGCAUUGGUCUGGGCCUUGAAUAAAAAACUGGUUACUUAGCAACCUGAGCCAGAAUAUAAUUUCAGGAGAAAAGAAUACUUCUGGUAAAAAAAAAAUUCCUUAUUGUUUGAAUUAUUAAAAACUGUAUCAUUACCCUUGGGAAAUUCAGUUCACCUCUAAGAAAAAGCCAAACCAAAAAGCAAAAGAAACAUGAAAUAUAUUAGAUAUGCGUCCCGUGGAAAUGCACACACAUUGGAGAAAUAGAACCAAAUCAUUCCCAUUGAUUUACAUUUUUUCAGUGUUUUUCAUCAACCAUCAUCAAAAUCCUAAAACCAAACUUUGCAAGACAUUUGGAGAUGUCCUUGGCAGCACUACUACUACUUGUUAGCGCACCUACCUUCAUUCAUAGGAUUGUGUCAGCAAAGGUUUUAACAACUAUGAAAACCCCACCUGUAUAGGAGAAUACAUUUUUUAUGGAUUUUUCUAGACAUGAUAUAUCCAUGACUUGCCGAGUUUUGGAUUAGCCUUUGUAUUCAUUUUCUAUGGCUGCAUAACAAAUUACCACAAAACUAGGAGAGCAAAACAACACAAAUUUAUUAUCUCACAGUUUCCAUGGGUUGAGAGCCCAGUGUGAACUGGAUUCUCAGCUCAGGGUUCCACAAGGCUGAAAUCAAGGUGCUGGCCAGCUGCAUCCUCAUCAGGAGGCUCAACUAGGGAAAGAUCUGCUUCCAAGGACCCUCAAUGUGUUGGCAAAAUUCAUUCCUUUGUGGCCAUAUGACUAAACUCCUUACAGGAGAGUCUCUCUUCCAGUUCAAAUUUCUUCUAAUCUCUUUUAAGUACUCACUUGAUUCGGUCAGGCCGACUCAAGUUAAUCUCUCUUUUUAUUAAUUCAAUGUCUGCUGAUUAGGGACCUUAAUUACAUCUGCAAAAUCUCUUCUGCGAUAUUACAUAAUAUAAUCAUGUGAGUGAUGCAUAGCCCAUCAUAUUUACAAGUCUUGUUCACGCUGAAAGAGGGCAUAAUACAGGGCAUGAACACGAAGGGGUGGGAAUAUUGGAGGUCAUCCUAGAAUUCUGCCUACUUUUGCCCUUUACUCAUUGCGUCCCUGUUUCUGUUGAGGAAAAUACUCCAUUUUCAAGACUGUUAUAAGGCCUAUAUAUGCACUUUUCAUUCAUUAAAGAAAAGUAUCACCAUG